AGGUUUCAGGCUUGCAUCCGGCUCCAGGAGUGAGCUGUAGCCUGUGGUCUAACCCAUUCCUCUUUUAAUCAUUGGGAUGGAAAGGCUUCUAGAAGGGUUAUCUGUUCCCACCGUCCUGGUUGGGCACAGUGAUGAGAGCCUGUCCCCUGUCUCAUGCUGCUUCAGCUCUCAUGGGAGGUUGAAUGGAGCAGCUGAACUUGGCUGACAGUGGCCUGGUGGGGAAGGAAGCCAGAAGAUGCAGAAGGGCCUCCCCUCCCAUGGGCAUGCCUUCUGCCUGGUGGCUGCAGAAUGAGGCCGGCUGCCUCUUUGCAGCAAGGCAGGUCAAUGGCCAGCAAGGAGGGGGGUCCGAGCCGGCGGCGGCGGCGGCAGUGGUGGCAGCGGGAGACAAAUGGAAACCUCCACAGGGCACAGACUCCAUCAAGAUGGAGAACGGGCAGAGCACAGCCGCCAAGCUGGGGCUGCCUCCCCUGACGCCCGAGCAGCAGGAGGCCCUUCAGAAGGCCAAGAAGUACGCCAUGGAGCAGAGCAUCAAGAGUGUGCUGGUGAAGCAGACCAUCGCGCACCAGCAGCAGCAGCUCACCAACCUGCAGAUGGCAGCAGUGACAAUGGGCUUUGGAGAUCCUCUCUCACCUUUGCAAUCGAUGGCGGCUCAGCGGCAGCGGGCGCUGGCCAUCAUGUGCCGCGUCUACGUGGGCUCUAUCUACUAUGAGCUGGGGGAGGACACCAUCCGCCAGGCCUUUGCCCCCUUUGGCCCCAUCAAGAGCAUCGACAUGUCCUGGGACUCCGUCACCAUGAAGCACAAGGGCUUUGCCUUCGUGGAGUAUGAGGUCCCCGAAGCUGCACAGCUGGCCUUGGAGCAGAUGAACUCGGUGAUGCUGGGGGGCAGGAACAUCAAGGUGGGCAGACCCAGCAACAUAGGGCAGGCCCAGCCCAUCAUAGACCAGUUGGCUGAGGAGGCACGGGCCUUCAACCGCAUCUACGUGGCCUCUGUGCACCAGGACCUCUCAGACGAUGACAUCAAGAGCGUGUUUGAGGCCUUUGGCAAGAUCAAGUCCUGCACACUGGCCCGGGACCCCACAACUGGCAAGCACAAGGGCUACGGCUUCAUUGAGUACGAGAAGGCCCAGUCGUCCCAAGAUGCUGUGUCUUCCAUGAACCUCUUUGACCUGGGUGGCCAGUACUUGCGGGUGGGCAAGGCUGUCACACCGCCCAUGCCCCUACUCACACCAGCCACGCCUGGAGGCCUCCCACCUGCCGCUGCUGUGGCAGCUGCUGCAGCCACUGCCAAGAUCACAGCUCAGGAAGCAGUGGCCGGAGCAGCGGUGCUGGGUACCCUGGGCACACCUGGACUGGUGUCCCCAGCACUGACCCUGGCCCAGCCCCUGGGCACUUUGCCCCAGGCUGUCAUGGCUGCCCAGGCACCUGGAGUCAUCACAGGUGUGACCCCAGCCCGUCCUCCUAUCCCGGUCACCAUCCCCUCGGUGGGAGUGGUGAACCCCAUCCUGGCCAGCCCUCCAACGCUGGGUCUCCUGGAGCCCAAGAAGGAGAAGGAAGAAGAGGAGCUGUUUCCCGAGUCAGAGCGGCCAGAGAUGCUGAGCGAGCAGGAGCACAUGAGCAUCUCGGGCAGUAGCGCCCGACACAUGGUGAUGCAGAAGCUGCUCCGCAAGCAGGAGUCUACAGUGAUGGUUCUGCGCAACAUGGUGGACCCCAAGGACAUCGAUGAUGACCUGGAAGGGGAGGUGACAGAGGAGUGUGGCAAGUUCGGGGCCGUGAACCGCGUCAUCAUCUACCAAGAGAAACAAGGCGAGGAGGAGGAUGCAGAAAUCAUUGUCAAGAUCUUUGUGGAGUUUUCCAUAGCCUCUGAGACUCAUAAGGCCAUCCAGGCCCUCAAUGGCCGCUGGUUUGCUGGCCGCAAGGUGGUGGCUGAAGUGUACGACCAGGAGCGUUUUGAUAACAGUGACCUCUCUGCGUGACAGUGGUCCCUCUCCCCGGACUUGCACUUGUUCCUUGUUUCCUCUGGGUUUUAUAGUGAUACAGUGGUGUCCCCGGGGCCAGGCGCGCUCUGCCCAGCCCAGCCUACAGUGCGGAUAAAGGUGCGGAUGCUGCUGGCCCUGAACGUCCGUGUGUCUGCCGUCGGUCCUGUCACCGA